GAGGCCAAGGUGGGCAGAUCACUUGAGGUCAGGAGUUCGAGACCAGCCUGGCCAACAUGGCGAAACCCCGUCUCUACUAAAAAUACAAAAACUAGCCGGGCGUGGUGGUGGGUGCCUGUAAUCCCAGCUACUUGGGAGACUGAGGCAGGAGAAUCACUUGAACCAAGGAGGUAGAGGCUGCAGUGAGCCGAGAUCACGCCACUGCACUCCAGCCUGGGUGACAGAUAGAGACUCUGUCUCAAAAAUAAAACAAAACAAACACUUUCCACCCAUGGACACCGCCAAGUCUAAGUCAGAGUCUCCUAAAGAGCUCGUACAGCUGAAGAAGCUCUUCAUUGGAGGGCUGAGCUUUGAAACAACCAAUGAGAGCCUGAGGAGCCAUUCUGAGCAAUGGGGAACACUCGCGGACUGUGUGGUAAUGAGAGAUCCAAACACCAAGCACUCCAGGGGCUUUGGAUUUGCCACAUAUGCCACUGAGGAGGAGGUGGAUGCAGCCACGAAUGCAAGGCCACACAAGGUGGAUGGAAGAGUUGUGGAACCAAAGAGAGCUGUCUCAAGAGAAGAUUCUCAAAGACCAGAUGCCCACUUAACUAUGGAAAAGAUAUUUGUUGGUGGCAUUAACGAAGACACUGAAGAAUAUCACCUAAGUGAUUAUUUUGAACAGUAUGGAAAAACUGAAGUGAUUGAAAUCAUGACUGACCAAGGCAGUGGCAAGAAAAGGGGCUUUGCCUUUGUAACCUUUGAUGAUCAUGACUCCGUGGAUAAGACUGUCAUUCAGAAAUACCAUACUGUGAAUGGCCACAACUGUGAAAUUAGGAAAGGCCUGUCAAAGCAAGAGAUGGUGAGUGCUUCAUCCAGCCAAAGAGGUCAAAGUACUUCUGGAAACUUUGGUGGUGGUCGUGGAGGUGGUUUCGGUAGGAAUGACAACUUUGGUUGUGAAGGAAAUUUCAGUGGUCAUGGUGGCUUUGGUGGCAGCUGUGGUGGUGGUGGAUAUCGUGCAGUGGGGAUGGCUAUAAUGGAUUUGGUAAUGAUGGAAGCAAUUUUGGAGGUGGAAGCUACAAUGAUUUUGGCAAUUACAACAAUUAGUCUUCAAUUUUUGGACCCAUGAAGGGAGGAAACUUUGGAGGCAGAAGCUCUGGCCCCUAUGGUGGUGCAGGCCAAUACUUUACCAAACCACGAAACCAAGGUGGCUAUGGCGGUUCCAGUAGCAGCAGUAGCUAUGGCAGUGGCGGAAGAUUUUAAUUAGGCAACAAAGCUUAGCAUGAGAGGAGAGCCAGCGAAGUGACAGGGAAGCUACAGGUUACAACAGAUUUGUGAACUAAGCCAAGCACAGUGGUGGCAGGGCCUAGCUGCUACAAAGAAGAUAUGUUUUAGACAAAUACUCAUGUGUAUGGGCAAAAAACUCGAAGACUGUAUUUGUGACUAGUUGUAUAACAGGUUGUUUUAGUUUCUGUUCUGUGGAAAGUGUAAAGCAUUCCAACAAAGGGUUUUAAUGUAUUUUUUUUUUUUGCACCCAAGCUGUUGAUUGCUAAAUGUAAUAGUCUGAUCGUGACACUGAAUAAAUGUCUUUUUAAAAAAAAAAAACAACAAAAAAACCACCAAUUUUAAAUAAUUCAUGGGUCAAAAAAGAAAACAAGACUAAAAUCUUGGAUUAUUUAGAAAUUAUAAUAAUGAAAAUAUUGCAUAAUGGAAUCCAUGAUAUUAAAGCACUUCUCAGAGGAAAAAUCCUAUAAGUAACCUUAUAUGCUUUCUUUUUAAAGUGAAAAUUAGUAAGCUAAGCAUUCAACAAAUAUAGAAGACAAUUAAAGGAAAAUGGCAGAGUAAACAAUCAGAAAUAAGGGAAAAAGAGCUGUACUUUAAAUAGAUUGAAAAGCUCAUUCUUCAGAAAUAAAGCAGAUACUAAUAUACACACAUUUCUGGCAAAAAAUAAUUUUUAAAAAAGGGACAUCCUCUUGGAUGUUUCAUAAACAAUUCAAACUUAGCUAAUCAAAUCUGAUUUUCCUGUCAAAUACUUAUUUCUUCUCCUGUUUUAAAUCUCAACAAAUUGUACCACCAUUUAAGUCAAAACCCAGGAGUUACUCUUUUUAAAGAAAAAUUUUUGGCUGGGCACGGUGGCUCACACCUGUAAUCCCAGUACUUUGGGAGGCCGAGGUGGGUGGAUCACAAGGUCAAGAGAUCAAGACUAUCCUGGCCAAUUAGCUGGGCAUGGUGGCACGCUCCUGUAAUCUCAGCUACUUGGGAGGCUGAGGUAGGAGAAUCACUUGAACCCAAGAGGCAGAGGUUGCAGUGAGCCAAGAUCGCACCACUGCACUCCAGCCUGGUGACAGAGUGAGACUCCAUCUCAAAAAAAUAAAAAUAUUGGCCGGGUGUGGUGGCUCAUACCUGUAAUCCCAGCACUUUGGGAGGCUGAGGCAGGUGGAUCAUCUGAGGUCAGGAGUUCGAGACCAGCCUGACCAACAUGGUGAAACCCUGUCCCUACUAAAUACAAAACAUUAGCCAGGUGUGGUGCUACAUGCCUGUAAUCCCAGCUACUUGGGAGGCUGAGGCAGGAGAAUCGCUUGAAUCCGGGAGGCGGAGGUUGCAGUGAGCUGAGAUUGCCCCAUUGCACUCCAGCCUGGGCAACAAGAGCGAAACUCCAUCUCAAAAUAAUAAUAAUAAUAAUAAUUUGUAGAGGCAGGGUUUCCCUGUGUUGCCCAGGCUGGUCUCAAACUCCUUGCCUCUGGCAAUCUUCCCACCUUGGCCUUCCAAAGUGUUGGGAUUACAGGUGUGAGCCACCAGGCCUGGCCCAGGAUUUAUUCUUCACACUUCUCUCCCCCAUUCAAUCCACUAUCAGGAUAUGUCUCUUCUGUUCCUAUAAUGAACAUGUAUGGAAUCAUCUCCCCAGCAUUCUCCCCUUUAUUUUCACUUGGAAAAUGCCCCUUACUCCCACUCAAAAGUACUUUUUUCUUUUCUUUGUUUUCUUUCCUGUGUCACUCCUUUAUUUUGCUAUUUUCCCCUCAGGUGCAGAGAAUUGAGCCAGUCAUACUCGUUUAUUCACACUGUCAUUAACAAGCCCUUUCUCAUUUUAUCUUUUCUCUUCAUUCCAGUUCCCACUAAUGUUCCUUUCCUCCCUCCUUAGGUAUUCACUCUAAUGUGUUUGAUAUAUGUCUUUGAAUAUACAUGUAUCUUUGAAUAAUAUGUAAUGUUUUAUGUAUGUAUGUGUUUUAAAUGUACCUAAUUGAUACUGUGUUACAGAUCUCAUUCUGUUUCUUUUUCAUGUUUAUGUAAAUACUUCUGACUAUUGCACACUGUUAUCUUCAGUGACCUCAUACCCUGGCCACUGGUCCUGGGCCAAGAUGGGCCAGAGUCCUUACCCAGAAUUUUUUUAACUGAAACUGAGAAAGAAAAUUCCCCUUCAGUGUGGAAGCCAUAAAAUGUAAAACAUACGAGCUGUCAGCAGCCACGUGUCAGUUGGUUCCAUAUGGAACCAACUCGCCUGUGUGAAAAAGAAGCCGACGUGCAGAAAGCAGCAGAGAACCAUGUGUGCUCAGUAUUGCAUCUCCUUUGCUGAUGUUGAAAAAGCUCAUAUCAACAUUCGAGAUUCUAUCCACCUCACACCAGUGCUAACAAGCUCCAUUUUGAAUCAACUAACAGGGCGCAAUCUUUUCUUCAAAUGUGAACUCUUCCAGAAAACAGGAUCUUUUAAGAUUCGUGGUGCUCUCAAUGCCGUCAGAAGCUUGGUUCCUGAUGCUUUAGAAAGGAAGCCGAAAGCUGUUGUUACUCACAGCAGUGGAAACCAUGGCCAGGCUCUCACCUAUGCUGCCAAAUUGGAAGGAAUUCCUGCUUAUAUUGUGGUGCCCCAGACAGCUCCAGACUGUAAAAAACUUGCAAUACAAGCCUACGGAGCGUCAAUUGUAUACUGUGAACCUAGUGAUGAGUCCAGAGAAAAUGUUGCAAAAAGAGUUACAGAAGAAACAGAAGGCAUCAUGGUACAUCCCAACCAGGAGCCUGCAGUGAUAGCUGGACAAGGGACAAUUGCCCUGGAAGUGCUGAACCAGGUUCCUUUGGUGGAUGCACUGGUGGUACCUGUAGGUGGAGGAGGAAUGCUUGCUGGAAUAGCAAUUACAGUUAAGGCUCUGAAACCUAGUGUGAAGGUAUAUGCUGCUGAACCCUCAAAUGCAGAUGACUGCUACCAGUCCAAGCUGAAGGGGAAACUGAUGCCCAAUCUUUAUCCUCCAGAAACCAUAGCAGAUGGUGUCAAAUCCAGCAUUGGCUUGAACACCUGGCCUAUUAUCAGGGACCUUGUGGAUGAUAUCUUCACUGUCACAGAGGAUGAAAUUAAGUGUGCAACCCAGCUGGUGUGGGAGAGGAUGAAACUACUCAUUGAACCUACAGCUGGUGUUGGAGUGGCUGCUGUGCUGUCUCAACAUUUUCAAACUGUUUCCCCAGAAGUAAAGAACAUUUGUAUUGUGCUCAGUGGUGGAAAUGUAGACUUAACCUCCUCCAUAACUUGGGUGAAGCAGGCUGAAAGGCCAGCUUCUUAUCAGUCUGUUUCUGUUUAAUUUACAGAAAAGGAAAUGGUGGGAAUUCAGUGUCUUUAGAUACUGAAGACAUUUUGUUUCCUAGUAUUGUCAACUCUUAGUUAUCAGAUUCUUAAUGGAGAGUGGCUAUUUCAUUAAGAUUUAAUAGUUUUUUUUGGACUAAGUAGUGGAAAAACUUUUAUACUUAACUGAGACAUUUUGUCAAGGCUAAAAAAAAGUCUUGCAAAAUGGGGCAGUGGACUGACAGGCUGACAUAGAAAAUAAACUUUGCCCAAUCACAACUUGUGCCUCCCAUCCCUGGAGUACUGACUGGCACCGGUAAGACAGAAUCUCUUUGAAUCCAUUACUCCAUGCCCCCUUGAGGCACUGUUGAAGAAAUCUCACUUUUCAGCCAGGGUACUGGUUCUGGUACAUAUGGAUCAUAAGUCCAUUUGGGGAAGACUCGUUUAUACAGGUUCAUCAGUACUGUGUCUUGAGAUUUUAGCUUCCCAUCAAAGCUGCAUUUCAUGUGGCCAUGGGUACCUAGAAAGACAUCAGAACAAGUCGGUCAAAUUAAAAGUAGAAAAUUUUAAAGCAAUGACUUCCAACCCAACAGUCAUUUAGCAACACUGCAGAAAUGCAGACAUGGUCUCAAAUCCCGUGUUUCCUUACCUAAAGGUUCCUUGAUAUGUCCUCUCCGGCCCCACUUCGUUCUCAGUUCCACUGGUUUAAACCACAGCACAUCCUCUUAGAAUCAAACACAUUAAAGACCAAGAUGAAACAUUUACCCACAAAAUGUAAACCCAACCUUUAUACCACAAAGGCAAUCAGAUCCCAUCCUCCUCCUUCAUACCCACCUCUGUUGAAGAACAUGUAACGUACUACUGCCAUCUUAGUAAAAAUUUUGAAAGGAUGACCACUCAGAACAACUCUCUUGAUGACCAUUCUGUCUGGAUCUACUGACAUAAGAUGGCCUGUAGCAAUGAGGCUGUGCAUUCCUAAAGGACAAAAGCAAAGAAGCUAUUUAGGAAUUUACAGGCCAAAGUCUUCAUUUAUUGCCCAGUCCAUUUAAAGACCCAUGCAAGAGCCUGGUUUGUCAUCCCUGCCCUAGCCCAAUCUGAGGCUAAGAUUGGUAAACUGUAAGCCCACACUUAACCUUGUCAAUAGGUUCUUGAAAACUUGUACUUCAAGAGAAAUGAUGUAUAACAAAACCAUACUUUUUCUCAUCAGUUGUUACAAGGAAAGGAUGUUGAACAAAAGGCAGUUAUUUGAGGACUGGCUAUACACUGUUUCACGUAAAAGUUGGAGUUUUCAUUGUUCUAUUAACAAUGUUAAAUGAAGACUUACUGUAUUUUGAAAACCAUCAUUACCUUCUCCAUACCAUUUGGCUCCCAAAUUUAAAUAAACAAGAGAAAACGGUGUUCAUCUAUUAA